AGAAAGGGACGGGGCUGGCAAAGGCCUGGUCUACCUCACCGAUCCGGGUCGCGGGGGCUCCUAGGGGGUUCCUUCCACAGCUGGUGCGCGUGCGCAAGAGUGCGUCGAGGUUGUUCCGCGGCAAUUUAUGAAACUCGGAGCCGGCAGUGAGUUGAGGGUUCGGCGAGGUCAGGGAUUCCUAGUUGCAGCGUGAUUACCAACGCCAGCUCCCUUCACUGUCCAAGACAGCGAUUCCGCGGCUCCUCUGAGAACUGGCGCUUGUGAGUGACUGAACGGGCCACUGGAGAGGAGCGGUGCUCACGGGUAUCGUUCUCGUCAGCGGGCGGUGGGGACGCGGGGUCUUGGAAUUGGGAAUCACGCUUGAGGGCGUCCAUGCGGAACGUGCAGCUUACCUCAGCUUGCUUGCAGUUACCCAGUUUCCACGCUGCCCUCCAAGUGUUCAUCAUUUGCCACUUAAGCUACUUGCAGUCACGUCACACCUUGGAUCUCUAUCAUCAAAACUAUUCCACCUCGGAAAUCUUACCUAAAUGCAGCAUGCCAUCCUGAACGUCUCUCCCUGUCCUAGCUCUGUAACUGUUUACAGUGAGUAAUUCAUUAAUUUGUGUUUUUCACCUACAAACCUCCCAGUAUAUUUGUUGCUUUUUUUUUAUUUCCUGAGUUGGAUAUUUAAUGCAUCUCAUUCUUGUUUAAUUAUAUGUAAGGCUUUUCCAUUGCCUAUCAGGAGCUUCAGCUGUGCGCUUUAGAUUUUGACGUACAAUGUUUUUACUGUUUUUAGAUACUUUGCAGUUGUCCUUUUGAUUCUCUUUUAUCUUUUUUUUUAGAAGCAAACAUUUGAAUUUUAAAGUAGGUGAAAUUGUUUUUUCUAUGUGGUGUUAAUUUCUGGUUUUGCAUUCUAGUAAUAAAUAUGGUUUCCACUACUCUUGUUUACCAUUUAUCAAGGAUUUUCUAUUUGGUAGCCUAAUAAAUUGCUUUUGUAAACAUUCCCUUAGGUGCUUGAAUAGAAACUACAUUUUAUCUAGUUUUAUUUAUCUAUUAGGCUAAGCAUAUUAUUUAUAUCCACUAUACUAUUACUUUUUUGACUUUAUCUGUCAGAGUCUGAGAAAGUUACCUAAUAUCCCAUUUCUAUUGUAUCACUGUUGACUUCAUUUCUUGUUUUCUGAGAAUUUUGCCAAAAAUGUUUCAAGUAUGUUGUACAUUUAAUGAGUUAUAUUUCAUUAUGAGUUAUAAUCAUUUAGUUUCCUCUAAUGUAUUUGUGCUUUUAAUUCAUUAUAAUUUUAAUUCACUAAACUCUUGAAUAUUUUUUGUUUGCCUGGUAUUUUUUAAAAAUUCUUUUACAUUUAGUUUUGGAGUUCUCGUUUCGGAUGUCUUUUGAGUUUUAUGUAGUUUGAGUUUAAAUUUUUACCCGGUACAUUUAUUGUUGCAAUUAACAUCUCUGUUAUUUUUACUUUUUAGUAUAAAGCCUUUUCUGUUUUGUCUUUGACAUAUGGCCUGUGAGCUUUUAUUUUUUCUUUCUCCAUUUAUGUUACUUUCAAAGUAUCUGGGCCCAUAGUUCAUUUUUUUGUUGGACUAAAUUAUACUACUUCAGGACUAUUCCACCAGUCAUAUUUAAGAGCUCUCUCUUGGCUGGUGGCUCAAAAGUGGAGCUAAUGAGGCCAGAUCAGGAGGGUCGUGGAUGUCAACAGUUGUGGCGGGUUUUCAGUCUGUUGUAUUGACGGUGGGCCUUGGCAGCUGCGAAUGAGGAGAAAGAUGGUCUUUUGUUAUGAGUUUGGGGAGAUGUCAAGGAGUACUCCAGAGGGAUUCAUUACAGGAAGCACUUGUUUCAGGGCAACUGGAAGCAAUUUUCUAUCCCGCGAGACCCAGGAAUAGCCCAUGAAAGGCACCAUUACCCUUUUCCUCCCCUGGCCAUGACAACCUAGAUGGGAUCUUUCAAGCCAGAAGGCACCUGCCUCUGUGGCUUUCCACUUGCUGUGGGAAAUCCUCUGGGGAGCUUGCAUUCACAGAGAAAAAAAGUUUCUAAAUAAAUUGGAUAAAGUUACAGGAAAAUAGAGAAGACAGUACAACAGAGUGUCCAUAUACCCCUCCACUAAUUUUUCCUAUUAGUAACAUUUUGUAUUAGUAUAGAACAUUUCUUACAAUUAAUAAUACUACAUUAACUAAAGUCCAUGCUUUAUUCAAGUUUAAUUUUUACCUAAUGUCUUUUUUACUGAUGUAGAAUCCAUCCAGUAUACCACAUUACAUUCUGUUGUCAUGCCCCCUUAGGCUUCUCUUGGCUGUGACAGUUUCUCAGACAUUCCUUGUUUCUGAUCAUGCUACAAUUAUGAGGAGGUAUUGGUUAAGUAUGGAGAACCAUCUGUUGGAAUUUGAUGUUUUUCUCAUUAUUAGACUGGGGUUAUGGGUUUAGAGCAGGAAGAUCACAGAGGCAAAAUGCCAUUUUAUCACAUUGUCUCGAGGCUACAUACUGCCAACAUGACUUAUCGCUAUUAAUGUUAAUCUUGAUCACCUGGCUGAGAUGGUAUUUGUCAGGUUUUUCCACUGUAAAUUUACCUUCCCCCUCCCCCCACCCCACAGCAUUUCCUCUUUGGCAGGAAAUUCCUAUGCAGAGCCCAUACUCAAGGGGUGGGGAGUUAUGCUGUACCUCGUGAAUGGCUGAGAAUUUGCAUAAAUUAUUUGGAAUUUUUCUGCAUAGGAGAUUUGUUUACUCUCCCCCAUGUAUUAAUAAGUUGCCAUUUAUAUCACUGCCUUAUGAGUAUUAAUUUAAUUGUUUGAAUUAUCUAAUAUUCUGUUGCUUAUAUUGUUCCAGAUUUGGCCAUAAGGAGCUCUUUCAUUUGGCUCCUGUGUACCUUUGAUGUGCCCCAAUAAAUGUUUCAGUUUCUUUUUUUUUUUUUUAAUUUUUUGAGCAUUUCUUUACUUUCUGGCAGUACAAGAUGCCCCAUGCUUAUGUUGCAUGAGCCUCAGUCCUAGAAUCAACCAUUUCUCCAAGAAAUCCUGGUUCCUAUUGGAGAAUGGUAUUAGAAACCAAGAUCUGGGAGCUAAUUAUUCUUUUGCUGCUGGGCUGUUCUUGCUUCUAGACCUACUUAGCCAACACAGCAAGGAAAUGUGUGUUUAUACUAAUUUAUGUAUAUAUACAUAUCUGUAAAUAUUUAUGUAACCAUCUUCAUCUAAUUCAGCCAAAUACAAGUUCACACUUAGGUCUCCAACUCUAAUCCAUUAUCACAUGGAUCAUUCUAGUCUCCUUCCCUUGGUUUUCUGUAAAUUUCUAGUCAAACAUUGAGAAACCUGGCUCUUACCACUCAUCUGCCAUUAAACUGUCUUUUCAUAGUUCUGUGUAUCCUUCCCCUACUCUGUGCGCUGAUACUUAUUUGAAUGUUGAAUGAUCUGUGCAGGCAGGCAUUGCCAUGGACAAGGUCACACAAACUUUUGGCCAAUAUGUAAGAUCUAACAUUGUAACAUACAUGUGUGCAUAUGAUCUACUGAGAGCUUACUGUGUGUCAAGAAAUGAGAUGAUAGCUCUUUUAAUCCCUAUAAUUUGAUCAGAUAUUUUUAUAUCCAUUUUACAGUUGAGAAUGCAAACUUGGGUUAAUAUAAUUUGCUCAGCUUUAUACAUAUAGUAACUAGUACAUCUGGGAUAGAAACUCAUGUAUCUAUGACUCCAAAGUAUGUAGUCUCAUUUAUAUAUUGCCUAUAGCAGAGUUUUUAAACCUUGGAAUUAUUGACGAUUUGGACUGGGUAAUUCUUUGCUAUAGGGGACUAUCCUGUGUAGGAUAUUUAACAACAUCCCUGGCUUUGACUUCCUAGAGGCCAGGUACAAUCUCUAGCUGUAACAGUCAAAACUGUUUCUAAACAUUGCCAGAUUUCCCCUGUUGGUAAAAUAUCCUGACUGAGAACCACUGACCUUAGAUAAUCAUAAUAAAAGUGACACCUGAAUAGUAAAUUGCAUCUGGACUUGGAGAACUGUAAAUCAAAUAGAAAGUUGUAUCUGGACAUCCCUGAAUGUAGUGACUCCUAUAAUUUGGCAGGCUCUUUGAGACAACCCAUAAAGUUGUGCUCAGUUGUUAUGAGAGAUACUGGCUCCUGGGGGAAUUCUUUUGAGUCAGAGUGUUUCCUACACCACGUUUAUGGGUCUCAUCUCCCUGUACUUGAGCUAAAUUCUGCAAAGACUCACACUGAAGAAAAGUGCAUAUUAUUCUUCUGCUAGCAAGUUGUUUUUUGCCUUCUGAGUAAAUUGGUGCCAAAUAUGACCUAUGGUAGUCUUGCAAGUCUAAAUGUUCAGUUGCGCCUAAGACAUCCCUGGUGGGCAUUGCGUAAUUCUCCAUAGUAACUCCUAACAAAUAUAAACUUUUCAUUGUAGUCUGGGAAUCCACUUUUUGAUUUAUUCCUAAUAAUAGUUUAUGGAUAUUAUUCUAGUAUAUUUUAAACAAUUGUCUCUUACCUUAAUUUCUAAUGCUAUUGUCAGUUUUACUCAUAGAAUUUUAUUGGCAUUUUAAAGAGAACUUUGGGUAAGGUUUUUCAGUCAUAUCUAUUCUGAAACCUUAAUAUCCUACCUGAAGAUUUGUGUUGCUUAAUUUUAAGGUAAAAAUGAUUUGCUACCUGAUAUAGAAUAAAUCUAAUUGUAAUUCAAUUACGAAGUUUUUUUAAAUCAAAGGACUCUUCAUCAUUUGUUUUGGGAUGUCUAUUCGUGUGUGUUUCUUUGUCCUUUGGGAAACUGGUUAGGAGAAAGGGAAAGCAUAUUUUCUAGUUCUAAGAAAGGAAAAUAAAAAUAGGAGAAUCCAUAAUAUGCAUUUUUCUUAGGCAAUUUUAAUAAUAUUUGUGUUUUAACACUAUGCUAAUAGAUGUUUGUUCCCUGUGGGUUAAUUUCUAUCUUUUUUCAGUUGCUCAGGUACCUGAAUAUUGGCUUUGUGUCUAAAGUUUCUGGAACUUUCCUCCUUACCGUGAAAUAACUUGGCUUAAAUCACACUGCAUAUAGUACACAGGUGCUUAGCUCAAGCCUGAGAAUUACUGCAAUCUAGUAAGGCGGAUUUGAACUACUGUGGGAGUUCUAUUUAGGAAGAUGCAGCCUCUGAGCAAGUUGAUGGCUAUCUCAAAACCUCGAAACCUGUCUCUACGUGAACAAAGAGAGGUUCUGAGAGCAGAUAUGUCUUGGCAGCAGGAAACCAACCCCGUCGUGGAGACACAUGACUCUGAGGCAUCUCGUCAAAAGUUCAGACAUUUCCAGUAUUUGAAAGUGUCUGGGCCCCAUGAAGCCCUGAGCCAACUCUGGGAGCUCUGUCUUCAAUGGCUGAGACCAGAGAUUCAUACAAAGAAGCAGAUUAUAGAACUGUUGGUGCUGGAACAAUUCCUGGCAAUCCUGCCUGAAGAAGUCAGGACUUGGGUGAAUUUACAACAUCCAAACAACAGUAAAGAUAUGGUGACCCUCAUAGAAGAUGUGAUUGAAAUGCUUGAAGAUGAAGAUAUGCCCUGCAAGGACUCUGCCCUGCAGAUGGGGAGCAUCAAGGAGAAAAUGAAAGCUGGCUCACGAACAGGCAAACCACAGGAACCAGUGACAUUCAAAGAUGUGGUUGUGGAAUUCAGCAAGGAAGAGUGGGGGCAACUGGACUCUGCUGUAAAGAACCUGUACAGGAAUGUGAUGCUGGAAAACUUUAGGAACCUGAAUUCAUUGCGUAAAGCACAUCUACUUUCCAAACCAUUUGAGAGCCUUAAGUUGGAGAGUAAGAAAAAAAGAUGGAUAAUGGAGAAAGAAAUACCAAGGAAGACUAUUUUUGACAUGAAGAGUAUUUCUGGAGAAGAAUCAUCCCAUGGAGUGAUUAUGACAAGGCUUACCGAAAGUGGACACCCUUCUUCAGAUGCCUGGAAAGGUGAGAAUUGGUUAUAUAGGAACCAGAAAAAAUGGGACAUAAAUUUGCCACAAGAGGCUUUCAUUCCUGAGACAAUUUACACUGAGGAGGAAGAUUUUGAAUGUAGUGAAAAUAAGAAAAGCUUUGAUAUUAAUUCAGUUAGCUCAAUUUGUGCUAUACAAGUGGGAAUUCCUUCAAGAAAGGGGUCUCCAAAAUGUGAUAAGUUUAAAACUUACUUCAAAUUUAAUUUAGACUCAGUAGGUAAGCAACAUUCAGAAUAUGAAUAUGGGAAUGACUUGAGUUUGAGUACAGAUAUUCGACACCAAAAAAGUCAUACUACAAUGAAUUCCUAUGAAUGUUAUCAAUGUGGGAAAGCCUUCUGCCGAAGUUCAUCCCUUAUUCGACAUCAGAUCAUUCACACAGGAGAGAAACCCUAUAAAUGCAGUGAAUGUGGGAGAUUCUUCAACCGACGUACAAACCUUACUAAGCAUCAAAAACUUCAUGCUGAAGCAAAGGCCUGCACAAGCAAUAAAUGUGGAAAGGCCUUCAGUAAAAGUGAAGACAGUAAUAAUCCAACACUCCAUUUUGGAAACAAUUUCUAUCAAUGUGUUAACUGUGGAAAAUCCUUCAACCGGAGCUCCUCUCUUAUUCGACACCAAAUGAUUCACACGGGAGAGAAACCAUUCAAAUGUAAGGAAUGUAGUAAAGCCUUCAACAGGAGUUCAAACCUUGUUAAACAUCAAAAACUGCAUACUCGAGAUAAGUCCUGAAAAAAGAAAAAAUGAAAGAUUACCUUCAGUCAGAAUGCAGAACUCAUUUAACAUCAUGAAUUUAUGCUGGAUAAAAUCUCAUGAAUAUAAUGUAAGAAAACAUUUGUCAGAUUUUUCUUUAAAUGAUAUCACAGAAUUAAUGUUGGAUAGAAAUAUCAUUGGAUAGAAAUCUGUUUGAAGGAAUUUUCCUGGUUUUCAGAUGAAGCCAUAAGGCUUUGGAGUUAAACCACAGUAUCACCAUACAAGUAUUUGUUUAUCAUUAUUUUGAUAUCCAUUACCCUCACCUCUCCCUAGUUCAUAAAUAGGUCUAUAGCAUACUAAUAUCCACCUGAUUUAUUGACGAAGUAGACAUUAGGCAAAGCCAAACAAUACUCUUGGAGUUGAUAUUUAAUAAAACUCAGCCCUUUUAAGAAGGUCACAAGAAAUCAUUAGCUCAUGCGAAUAUAAGAGAAUACUUCUAAGGACAGAAAUCUCUGAAUCAAUGGCUAAGACAACAGUAACAGCCAUUUACUCCACUCCUGACAAUACCCUUUGUUGUCUUGCUGUUGAAUGGAGACUAGAGUUGGGAAAGGGUUAUCAACUGCAAUGGGAGAAGUAUGUAUUGCUGUUAAUCUAUAUGUAUUCUUAAAAUCUGCAUUUGUUUAUAGCAGGUCCUUGAAAAAUGUUUUUGUUUUGUUAUAAUGUUAUAAUUGUUAUGAUGUUGAUGAGAAAAAUAUCGAUUCCCAGCCAGGGACACUGUGUGGAGUUCGCACACUCUCCCUAUGUCUCCGGGUGCUCCAGUUUCAAACCCCAAAGAUGUAUACAUUAGGUUAAUUGACAUAUCUAAAUUAUCUCAGUCUGAGUUUGUGAGGAAGUGUGCCCUGCAGUGGAAUGGCUCCUAAUCAGGGUUUGUUCCCACCAUUGCCCUGAGCUGCUAGGAUGCGCUCUGUCCACCCAUGGCCCUGUACUGGAAUAACAGGGUAAAUAAUUAUCUUAUCUGUUUUUAUUAAUCCGUCUUAAAUGUGUAUAUAGCUCAGAUUUAUUUUAAUGUCUGAUAUUGGAAGCGUUUGGGGUCUUUAGAAGUUUGAUGAUGUUGUGACCAGACAUUUGCCUUAGGAACUUAACUCUUGUUUGUAUCCAUUAGUCUAUGGUAAAAUUGGUUUUGUUAUACAUCAUUUCACUUAAAGUUGCAGUUCCUAAGAACCUAUUGAUGAUGUUCAGUGCAGACUUACUGUACCUUUGGGAAUUUAGGCUGGAGAGACGUCCAUAGCCUUAGGUAUAUCAUUUAUACCAGACAUUAUGAAGUUAUUAAAGUCUCCUAUACUCUGUACACCAGAACUGUGUCUUCUGUAAACUACCUCAGGAUCCCAUCUGGUUCUUGAGCCAAGAAGUAUGACUUAAUCUGCCCCAAAAAAUUCACACUGGAGACAUUCCCAAUUAAUGAUGAUGGUAGCUUUUUGUGAAGGUUCAUACCUUAUUCAAAGGCAGAAAAGGUAUACUGGAGUGAACUCCUAUGAUUAAAUAAUGUCAAAAUCUA